CUCUUUUUGCCUGCUGCCAUUCCAGUAGGAUGUGACUUGCUUCUCCUGGCCAUGGUUGUGAGGCCUCCCCAGCUAUGUGGAACUAUGUUGAGAAGGAACAACAUGAUCUAAGUCUUUAGAAACCAAGAGCCACGACUAGCUGAGGACACAAGAAUUUUCACAAAACAAAGUAGAGUGAUUCCAUAGAUCACUAUUAUAGCUGCAUUACCAGUCCUAGGACAGAAUAUGGAUGCUGAAAAAUGAUUCUUUCAAAGUGCUGAGUUGUUGCCUCACGCCCAGUUGUCUGGCAUCUCUUCACUGAAACUAUUACAGUUAGAUCUCAUCUCUAUGGGUGGAAGGAAAAAAUUCUGAGAAUGAUAUAGUCGAAGUGAUACCUUGAAGGUAGAACUGUGCACUGUGGUAAUAACAGAAACAGAAAGACAUUUCUUCUAUAUAAACCCAGGAUGUCGUCCAGCGGCAGCUCCCAUCCCUUCCUAUUGACUGGUUUUCCAGGCUUGGAGGAAGCUCAUCACUGGAUUUCCGUAUUUUUCUUGUUCAUGUAUAUAUCCAUCCUUUUUGGCAAUGGCACCCUCCUUCUUCUCAUUAAGGAAGAUCACAAUCUUCAUGAGCCCAUGUACUUCUUUCUGGCCAUGCUGGCUGCCACAGACCUGGGGCUGGCCCUGACCACAAUGCCCACGGUGCUGGGAGUCCUCUGGCUGGAUCACAGGGAGAUUGGAAGUGCGGCCUGCUUUUCCCAGGCCUACUUUAUACACUCACUUUCCUUUCUCGAGUCUGGCAUUCUGCUUGCCAUGGCCUAUGACCGUUUUAUUGCCAUCUGCAACCCUCUUAGAUAUACCUCUGUACUUACUAAUACUCGAGUAGUGAAGAUUGGGCUGGGAGUUCUGAUGAGGGGAUUUGUAUCCGUUGUUCCCCCAAUCAGGCCCCUCUAUUUUUUUCUGUAUUGUCACUCCCAUGUUCUUUCACAUGCAUUCUGCCUUCACCAGGAUGUCAUUAAACUCGCCUGUGCUGAUACCACCUUCAACCGACUGUACCCAGCUGUGCUUGUAGUCUUUAUAUUUGUGCUGGAUUAUCUGAUUAUCUUCAUCUCCUAUGUGUUGAUACUCAAGACUGUCCUGAGCAUUGCCUCCAGAGAGGAGAGGGCCAAGGCUCUCAUUACCUGUGUCUCCCAUAUCUGCUGUGUCCUGGUUUUUUAUGUCACAGUGAUUGGAUUGUCUCUGAUUCAUCGUUUUGGAAAGCAGGUUCCACAUAUUGUUCACCUCAUUAUGAGCUAUGCCUAUUUUCUGUUCCCUCCACUAAUGAAUCCUAUAACAUAUAGUGUCAAGACCAAGCAGAUUCAGAAUGCCAUUCUUCACCUUUUUACUACCCAUAGAAUUGGAACCUGAUCUCCAAUCAUCACAGUCACUCUCACAGAAUGUAAAAACUCUAAUAUUUAGCAGGAGAGCAAAGAAGUCUCA